AGUGGCCUUGACCUCCCGCGGCGUGGGAGGCUGCGCGGCGAUGCUGCAGUUCGUCCGGGCCGGGGCGCGGGCCUGGCUUCGGCCUACCGGCAGCCAGGGCCUGAGUUCCCUGGCGGAAGAGGCAGCGCGUGCGACCGAGAACCCGGAGCAGGUGGCGAGCGAGGGUCUCCCGGAGCCCGUGCUGCGCAAAGUCGAGCUCCCGGUACCCACUCAUCGACGCCCAGUGCAGGCCUGGGUCGAGUCCUUGCGGGGCUUCGAGCAGGAGCGCGUGGGCCUGGCCGACCUGCACCCCGAUGUUUUCGCCACCGCGCCCAGGCUGGACAUACUGCACCAGGUUGCUAUGUGGCAGAAGAACUUCAAGAGAAUUAGCUAUGCCAAGACCAAGACGAGAGCCGAGGUGCGGGGCGGUGGCCGGAAGCCUUGGCCGCAGAAAGGCACUGGGCGGGCCCGGCAUGGCAGCAUCCGCUCUCCGCUCUGGCGAGGAGGAGGUGUUGCCCAUGGCCCCCGGGGCCCCACAAGUUACUACUACAUGCUGCCCAUGAAGGUGCGGGCGCUGGGUCUCAAAGUGGCACUGACCGUCAAGCUGGCCCAGGACGACCUGCACAUCAUGGACUCCCUAGAGCUGCCCACCGGAGACCCACAGUACCUGACAGAGCUGGCGCACUACCGCCGCUGGGGGGACUCCGUACUCCUCGUGGACUUAACACACGAGGAGAUGCCACAGAGCAUCGUGGAGGCCACCUCUAGGCUUAAGACCUUCAACUUGAUCCCGGCUGUUGGUGAGCAAAGAGCCCAGGCCCCUAGAGUGCGCAUGUGCAGGCUCCGCUGUUAGAAUCACAGCGGUUCAAAUCCGGCAUCUGGUCGCUGAGUGGCCUCAGGCAGUGACCACGCUCCCGGACCCAACCUUCAGCUUGCCCAAAGCAAUAAUCUUUCCUAAAGAAGUGCUUGGCUGGGGAUGGUGGCUCACGCUUGUAAUCCCAGUACUUUGGGAGGCCAAGGCAGUCUGGGCAAUAUAGUGAGGCUCCCAUCUGUACUAAAAAUAAAAAAGUUAGGCGUGGCGAUGUGCACCUGUAGUCCCAGCUACUCGGGGGCUGAGCCAGGCGGAUAGCUUGAGCUCAGGGGGCCAAGGCUGCAGUGAGUCAUGAUCGCACCACUGCACCCAAACCUGGGGAGAGAGCUAGACUCUUGUCUCAAAAAAAAAAAAAAAAAAAAAAAAAAAGCUCCAAAGUCACCUCUGUCAAAGCCACAGUCUGUUCCUUCCACAGCCACAAGAUGGCGACAUGAGCCUAAGUCAAGUCCUGUCCCUCAACCCACGCCCCUCGCUGGCUUCCCCACCUCUCUCAGGAUGAAAGCCCAAGUCAUCAGGGUGGCACGUCAGGCCCUGCACGAUGUGCCCCGUCACCUCCCUGCCCUCCCGUCAUUUGCCCUGGGUCUCCCCCACCAGAAUGGGAGCCAGGAGUCCCAGCCAGGCACAGGACCGAGCCUGGCUCUCGGUCAGCAGGUGAUGAGCUGGGAGCAGCUCCUUGGCCAGAGGCUUACAGGCAACAAGCGGCCAGGCAGGGUCUGGCCCCGGGCUGCUGGGCUCACAAAGUCACACUAGACCACAGUGACGAUCUCUGUAAGCACAAAGGGACUCCGAUGUGGGUGGGGUGAGGAGAGAGGCAGCCCCGGCCUGACCGGCCCCCCGCCCCGCCCCCACCCCGCCCCCAGGCCUAAAUGUGCACAGCAUGCUCAAGCACCAGACGCUGGUCCUGACGCUGCCCACCGUCGCCUUCCUGGAGGACAAGCUGCUCUGGCAGGACUCACGUUACAGACCCCUCUACCCCUUCAGCCUGCCCUACAGCGACUUCCCCCGACCCCUACCCCACGCUACCCAGGGCCCAGCGGCCACCCCGUACCACUGUUGAUGUGAAGCACCUCUUCUGAGCCAGGCCGAGCCCCUGGCCGACUUGGGAGCCUCAGGCCCACGCCCACCCUUCGAGGAAGGUGUCACCUGGACCCCUUCAUUCCACGGAGGAAGCUGAGGCCACAGGGAGCGGCCAUCGCCAUUGGGAAGGGGCGACUCCACGGAAAGCCCAGACGGGCUUCUGCAUCCAUUCCCUCUUUUUGUUUUUAAAAUAAAUUGUAUUUUUGAAUCAAGGAGGAUAAA